ACUUAAGGCUUCCGGGCAUGCGCACAGCGUUGUGCAAAUGAAUGCCUUCCACUGAACCGAGGUAGACGGGGUCGAGUUUCUUGCGCGAUGGUGGGCUUGUAUGUGUGUGUGUGUGUGUGUGUGUGGGGGGGGGGGGUGACGAGGUUGGCAUUGAGGAUCCAUACCCUUUGCGCCCAAAGAAAGGUGACGUGGACUAGUGUCGUGCCUUUGGACAGGCAGAGUAAGAGGAGGGAGAAGAAACAGGUAGAGCUGCUGGCCUUGUCGGGGACACCUUUGGACGUGCUGGAGGGCAACGACGCCCUAGUUUUCUGUGAAGUUAAGUAGCUUCUGCAGGACUGGGUUCAGUAUUUCUAGUACCUUCUCAGGAUCCCUCCUCCGCCAACGAAUUCCUCAACCACGGGCCAAGCAAACUACUCCCCCGCCCACUGUCAGCAGCAGUCUCUGUUGAAUGGGAAUACUGCACCUUCAGGCUUAACGCCACGUGGGCUCCUUUGCUGUCCUCCAGGCACUGUUAUAGAAGAAUGGAAGAAGAUACAGAUUAUAGAAUCAGGUUUAGUUCUUUGUGUUUCUUUAAUGAUCACGUUGGAUUUCAUGGCACUAUAAAAAGCUCACCAAGUGACUUUAUUGUUAUUGAAAUUGAUGAACAGGGACAGUUAGUUAAUAAGACCAUCGAUGAGCCUAUUUUCAAGAUUAGUGAAAUACAACUUGAGCCAAAUAAUUUUCCCAAAAAACCAAAACUAGAUCUUCAAAAUCUGUCCUUAGAAGAUGGAAGAAACCAAGAAGUUCAUACUUUGAUUAAGUACACUGAUGGUGACCAAAAUCAUCAGUCUGGUUCAGAAAAGGAAGAUACUAUCGUUGAUGGAACUUCCAAAUGUGAAGAAAAAGCUGAUGUUUUAAGCUCCUUUUUGGAUGAAAAAACUCAUGAGUUACUGAAUAAUUUUGCCUGUGAUGUAAGAGAGAAGUGGCUUUCUAAAACAGAGCUAAUUGGACUACCUCCUGAAUUCUCAAUAGGCAGAAUCCUUGACAAAAACCAGAGGGCUAGUUUACACAGUGCCAUUAGGCAGAAAUUUCCAUUUUUAGUAACUGUAGGAAAAAACAGUGAAAUUGUUGUAAAACCAAAUCUUGAAUAUAAAGAACUUUGUCAUUUGGUAUCUGAAGAGGAAGCAUUUGACUUUUUUAAAUAUUUGGAUGCAAAGAAAGAAAAUUCCAAAUUUACCUUUAAACCUGAUACAAACAAAGACCACAGAAAAGCUGUCCACCAUUUUGUCAACAAAAAGUUUGGAAACCUUGUGGAAACCAAAUCUUUUUCUAAAAUGAAUUGCAGUGCUGGUAAUCCGAAUGUGGUGGUAACAGUAAGAUUUCGGGAAAAAGCACACAAACGUGGGAAAAGGCCUCUUUCUGAAUGCCAAGAAGGAAAAGUUAUAUAUACAGCUUUUACCCUACGAAAGGAAAACCUGGAAAUGUUUGAAGCGAUUGGUUUUUUAGCUAUCAAACUUGGUGUUAUUCCUUCGGAUUUUAGUUAUGCAGGCCUUAAAGACAAGAAAGCCAUCACCUAUCAAGCAAUGGUUGUUAGAAAAGUGACUCCAGAGAGGUUGAAAAAUAUUGAAAAAGAAAUUGAAAAGAAAAGAAUGAAUGUCUUUAAUAUUCGGUCUGUAGAUGAUUCCCUGAGACUUGGUCAGCUCAAAGGAAAUCACUUUGAUAUUGUCAUUAGAAAUUUAAAAAAACAAAUAAAUGAUUCUGCAAACCUGAGGGAGAGAAUUAUGGAAGCAAUAGAAAAUGUUAAGAAAAAAGGCUUUGUGAAUUACUAUGGACCACAGAGAUUUGGGAAGGGAAGGAAAGUUCACACAGACCAAAUUGGACUAGCUUUGCUGAAGAAUGAAAUGAUGAAAGCCAUAAAAUUGUUUCUUACACCAGAAGACUUGGAUGAUCCUGUAAAUAGAGCAAAGAAGUAUUUUCUUCAAACUGAGGAUGCUAAAGGCACACUUUCAUUGAUGCCUGAAUUCAAAGUGCGUGAGAGAGCAUUGUUGGAGGCAUUGCACCGCUUUGGCAUGACCGAGGAAGGUUGUAUCCAGGCAUGGUUCUCUUUACCCCAUUCCAUGCGCAUAUUCUAUGUUCACGCAUAUACCAGCAAAAUUUGGAAUGAGGCAGUAUCUUACAGACUUGAAACCUAUGGAGCAAGAGUAGUGCAGGGUGAUUUGGUCUGUUUGGAUGAAGACAUUGAUGACGAGAAUUUCCCAAAUAGUAAAAUUCACCUGGUAACUGAAGAGGAGGGAUCAGCUAAUAUGUAUGCAAUACAUCAGGUGGUUCUUCCAGUACUUGGAUACAAUAUUCAGUACCCGAAGAACAAAGUAGGGCAGUGGUACCAUGACAUACUUAGCAGAGAUGGACUACAGACAUGUAGGUUUAAAGUACCUACUCUGAAACUGAAUAUACCAGGUUGCUAUAGACAGAUUUUGAAACAUCCCUGUAAUCUCUCAUACCAACUAAUGGAAGAUCAUGACAUUGAUGUCAAAACGAAAGGUUCCCACAUUGAUGAAACAGCUUUGUCUCUUUUGAUCUCUUUUGAUCUUGAUGCUUCAUGCUAUGCUACCGUUUGUCUGAAGGAAAUAAUGAAGCAUGACGUUUAAAACUGAUACCCUUGGUAUAACCAUAUAUAUGUCACUCUUUGAAGGAAAGGGGGCUAAAAUGUCUUAAGCACCUUCCAUGUGUUAGGAACUUCAUAAUUGUUAUCUCUUUUAAUUUUCACAGCAUCCUGAGAAGUUAGGAUUUGAUACUGUAAUUUUAUAGAGGAUAUGUAAGUGUCAGGGUCCAAAUUUAAGGUCCAUGUGACCCCAAAGCCUGUGUUUUUUUUCUAUUAUAUGUUUCAGUGACCUUUAUUCUGUGUCAUAAAGUUACAAUCUUUUAAAACCAUUAGGAAUAUAUAUAAUACUGCAAGAUAACAUUUAAGAAAAAAAGUUGUGAAUAUUCAUAUCCUCCAGCUCCUUGCUUAGAACACUAGUAAAAUUAGGUCGCAGUGAAGCAAAUGUUGGAGAGAAAGAUAGAUGAAGCAUUUUGCUAAUUAUUAUUGUCCCCCUUUCCUGUUUUUGAAAUUAUUGAUCAGAACAAUAUACAAGGGAAAUGCCAUACCUCUGUUUGUGAUAGAUACCCCAGAGUAGUUAUUACCUCUUUGUGAGAUAAGUAAUCUUUGAUGAAGAUUGAAAUACAAUUUCUCAUCCAAUUUUUAUAUCUUGGCAUACGCUGACCCUCUUGACCAUUUGUAAUUUUUUCAUAUUAUCUAAAACAGGUGUUAGAGUCAGACAGAUUCAUUCUUAGAUUCUAGCUCUGACACUUACUAGUGAUUUUGAGUAUGUUGUUGAUUUUUUUGUGUGUGGUUACUGAUAGAAUCAAGACAAUUACAACUUCAUAAAUGACAAAUAAUAGGAUUAUCUCCACAUUUUCUGUUGCUGGAGGAACAAAACAUUGUGCCCAUUUGAAAAUUUUAAUUUUUGUUGGUUUAACUAUCCCACAUUAUAAAUCAUCCUUCACCAUUUUAUAUCAGUUAAAUAUGGGUGUGUUGGGGAGGAAUGACUGGCAUGUAGACAUGUAUUGAUUUAGGAAGAUCUGAGCAUUUCUUUCAUUGUUGGUAAGAUAUAAUGAUGAAAUUUAAAAAGCAGUAUGGAGCAUUAUAUAUCAGUAAUGUGAUAUAUAUACUUAAGCCAGUUUAACCAUUUUGGGAAAUGUUAGCAUUAGGAAAUAAAAUCCAAAAGAAGGAAGAGAAGCUAUAUGCAAUGCAAAAUUUGCUUAUUGCAAUAUUUUCAUAUACAGACACUAAAAACAGUUUUCAAAGUCCAGCAUUACGUAACUAAAGUAAGUAAAAUGAUGUGUAUCAACUUGAUGGUAAAAUAUGUAGUUAUUUAAAAAAGCAAUGAACAAUUUAGUUUCAUGAGAAAAUGUUGCCCCCUAAAAGUAGAACACAUAUGUUACAACUGCAAUAAUACUCUGAAUUCAUCUUUCACAAAUAAGAGACAUGUUAGCAUAGUGAUUAAAAGCACAGAUAUUGGAGACAAACUAACCCAGUUUGAACCCUGGCACUGCCACGUAUAGCACUGCAGCCUUGGGAAAGUUAUUUAAACUCAUGGGCUUCAGUUUCAACAUCUGUAAAAUGGGCAUGUUAACAUUGCCUACCUCAUAGGAUUACUGUGAGAAUUUUCUAAGUUAAUAUAUGUAAAGCAACUUUAAAAAGUGCCUGGCACUUAGUUAUUGUUAAGUAAGUGUCUGCAGAUGCAAGUUUGGAAGAGAAAAGCAAAUAAAUGAAAAUCCCUUCCUGUUAAGAUGAUGGGGUAUUUGGAUUUUUUUUAAUACUAAAAAGUUUUUUUUGUUAUAUGUUUUGGCAAUAAAUAAUUCUCAAUACACAAAAUUGGAUAUUGUAGUACCAUUGAUUUUCUUUGGAUUACUGCCAUCAUUUUAAUGUUAUAUUGAGAAUGAAGUGAUCCUCUAUUAGGUAGUAAAAAAAAUUUAGAAAAAAUGUUUUAUUUUAUAUGAUAAAUCGUAUCCUAUAAAUGUAAUCAUAAAAUGAGUUAUAUACAUUAUUAAAUCCUAGUUUUUAAAAGUUUUGAAUAGCAAUCAGAAAAUACGAAAGCAUGAAAAUAUAUCAUUGAUUUUACUUUUUUUGCCUGCAGAUGGCACUAUAAUUUUAGACAUUUAUUGAUUUAUUUAGUAAAUACUUCAGCAGUGUAUAAAGGAACACUAAGUUUAUUUCAUCACCAUAAAAUGUAUUGAGAUAUCAUUCAUGUGGAAUAUUAUUUUAUAUGCCAAUAAGAUGCCAUGUUAAACUUUUUUUGUUUAAGGACUUUUAUUAUUAAUAGUAUGCUUUGGACCAACUGAUGACUAGUCACUUAGGUUUUUGCAGUUUUGCUGGGGCAUUUCAGACCUUCAUAAGCAUGAUCUUUGGAUUAGUUUUUUUUUUUUCUUCACCUCAUUAUUAGGAGUUAAUUUAUUUUUAAAGUGUCAUCUUAAACUGCAAGGAUGUCCUUUAAACAUCACAUGCCAAUUAAACAUGCCGAAGGAGAAGCUGUGUCAUCAAAAUGCCCACUUAACCUACCCAAACAUCUCAAACCUACCCUUUGCUGACCUUCUAUAGCCCCAUUUCCAAAGUUUUGCUUUAUUUUUAUUUUUUCUUCCAACUUUUAUUUUAGGUUUAGGGGUACAUGUGCAGGUUUGUUACAUGGGUAAAUUGCAUUUUGUGGGAGUUCUGCAUACAAAUUAUUUAAUCACCCAGAUAAUGAGCAUAGUACCUGAUAGGUUGUUUUUCUAUCCUCAUCUUUCUCCCACCCUCCACCCUCAAGUAGGCCAUGGUGCCUAUUGUUCCCUUCUUAGAGUCCAAGUGUACUCAAAGUUCAGCUCCCACUUAUGAGUAAGAACAUUUGGUAUUUGGUUUUCUGUUCCUGCAUUAAUUUGCUUACAAUAAUGGCCUCCAGCUACAUCCAUGUUGCUGGAAAGACAUUAUUUUGUUCUUUUUUAUGACUGUGUAGUAUUAUCUGGUAUACAUGUACUACAUUUUCUUUAUCCAGUCCACUGUAAUGGGCAUCUAGGUUGGUUCCAUGUCUUUGCUAUUGUCAAUAGUGCUGUAAUGAACAUAGGCGUGCAUGGUCUUUAUGGUAGAACAAUUUAUAUUCCUUUGGGUAUAUAACCAAUAAUGGGAUUGCUGGGUCAAAUGGUAUGUCUGCUUUAAGUUCUUUGAGAAAUCUUCAAACUGCUUUCCACAGAGGCUGAACUAAUUUAUAUUCCCAUCAGCAGUGUAUAGCAUUCCCUUUUCUCUGCAGCCUCCCCAACAUCUGUUAUUUUUUGACUUUUUAAUAACAGCCAUUCUGACUGGUGUGAGAUGGUAUCUCGUUGUGGUUUUGAUUUGCAUUUCCCUAAUGAUUAGUGAUGUUCAGCAUUUUUUCAUAUGCUUUUGGCCCAUGGAUGUCUUCUUUUGAGAAGUGUCUGUUCAUGUCCUUUCUUCCGUUUUUAAUGGGAUAAUUUUUUGCUUGUUAAGUUCUUCAUAGAUUCUGGAUAUCAGACCUUUGUUCAUGCAUACUUUGAAAAUAUUCUCUCCCAUUCUGUAGAUUGUCAGUUUACUCUGUUGAUAGUUUCUUUGGCUGUGCAGAAGCUAUUUAGUUUAAUUAGGUCCCACUUGUCAAUUUUUUUUUUUUUUUAGAUGGAGUUUCCUUCUGUCACCCAGGCUGGAGUGCAGUGGUGCAAUCUCGGCUCACUGCAACCUCCUCCUCCUGGGUUCAAGCCAUUCUCCUGCCCCAGCCUCUCAAGUAGCUGGGAUUACAAGUGGCCACCACCACACCUGGCUAAUUUUUGUAUUUUUAUUAGAGACGGGGUUUCACCAUGUUGGCCAGGCUGGUCUCAAACUCUUGACCUCAAGUGAUCUACCCACCUCGGCCUCAGAAAGUGCUAGGAUUACAGGCAUGAGCCACCAUGCCCAGCCUUCACUUGUCAAUUAUUGGCUUUGUUCCAGUUGCUUUUGGAGUCUGUCAUGAUAUCUUUGUUAGGUCUUUUGUCCAGAAUGAUAUUUCCUAGGUUUUCUUCUAGGGUUUUUAUAGUUUUAGGUUUUACAUUUACAUUGUUAACCCAUCUUGAGUUGAUUUUUGUAUAUGGUAAAAAGAAGGGGUCCAGUUUCAAUCCUCAGGAUGUGGCUAACCAGUUAUCCCAGCACCAUUUAUUAAAUAGGGAGUCCUUUCCCUGUUGCUUGUUAUUGUUGACUUUAACAAAAAUCAAGUAGCUGUAGGUGUGUGGCCUUUAUUUCUGGGUUCUCUAACCUGUUCCAUUGGUCUAUGUGUCUGUUUUUGUACCAGUACCAUGCUGUUUUGGUUACUAUAGCCUUGUAGUUUAGUUUGAUGUCAGGUUGUGUGAUGCCUCCCUCAUUGCUAUAUUUGAAUUAGUUUUAAUUGCCAAGGUUGUUUGACGCUGAGCUAGCAGUAGUGCCUGGGAGUCGGUUAGGUGAAACAAAUUGAGGUCUUUUACUAAUAUUAAAAUUAAAACACCUUGAUUUUUUUUUUGUGAGCUGUAAAAAACUGAAAGUCAUGUAACUUUUGAUUUAACUAACAUUUUCUGAGUAUCUAUUAUGUCAGUAUCUCACACUUUAAUCCAUAUUCCCACCCUGUGUGGAGGUAUUAUCUUCCCUUAUUUGCAGAUUGGAAACAUACCUGAGUAGUUUACUAACCUAAUCAAGGUCAAACAAAAUAGCGUGUGGUUGAGCUUGAUUAUGCUUCUUAAAUCAGUACUGUUUUCAUCUACCUAACAUUUGCCUUCUGAGAACAAGUUUUUGGAUAUUAACUUCCAUUUAGGCCAGGCACGGUGGCUCACGCCUGUAAUCCCAACACUUUGGGGAGGCCAAGACGAGUGGAUCACGAGGUCAGGAGUUCAAGACCAGCCUGGCCAAGAUGCUGAAACCCUGUCUCUACUAAAAAUAAAAAAAUUAGCUGGGCUACUUGGGAGGCUGAGGCUGGAGAAUCGCUUGAACCCGGGAGGUGGAGGUUGCAGUGAGCCGAGAUUGCCCAGCCUAGGUGACAGAGCGAGGCUCCACCUCAAAAAAAAAAAAAAACUAAACUAAAAAUUAAAAUAUAACUUCCAUUUCUACCAACUUGAUAUAACUUGCCAUUGAUUUAAUAGGCAUAUUGGGGCAUGUCUUGGGAGAGACAAGAUACCUUUUGAUUCUGAGACCAAAAUAUAAAGUAAAGGGGAUCCCUUCAGGAAAUCCCCAAAUCAUUUUGGAGUUUUCCCAAAGUAUUUUGGGAUUUGUAUCAUAAUAAUAUGUAAAAUCAUUAUAGAUCAUAGGAGGUGUUUUAGAUGGUACCUGGCACAAAUAUCAUUGAAAAAGCAUAGUGAGAAACUUGUUCUUUUUCAAUAUACUUUCAGUCCUCACAUCAAUCAUUCUGUUUAAGGAAGGAGAAAGCUGAUUGAUACUAUUUACAUAUAUCAACAUUGGCUGAUUUACCUUUUUAGCCAACUAUGCAGGCCUCAGGCUCAGAAACAUCAGCAGUCAACAAUAUAAUAUGUAGCUAGAAUGUAAUAGGAUUGCAUUGUUUUAUUGAAUUUAUCUUCCCUUUUAUUUAUGGUAAUCAAUUCUGGCUUCCUGUUUAUGUGAUGGUAUUAUGUUUCCUUUAAAACUAAAUUUAAUUUUAAAGAGGUAGAAUCAAUUUAAAGGUAUUAAAUAAAUAAUAGUAUAGACAUAGCAGUAAUUAUGAUACCAAUACAUGAAGGAUUAGAGUAUGGGAAAUAUACUGGUACAGUUGAGAAUCCCUGAAAUCAGAGAUGGGCUCUACCACUGCUUUAAUAUGCGACUUUAGUAACCCACUGAUUCUGUUGUAGAAUUCUUGGACUUGAAGUACUGUUAGUUAUCAUUUUUCAGUCCAGGAUAGUAUUGCAUCAAACAAAAUUAUGAAAUAUAUACAAAUUUGAGACAUUAUGAGCAGAGGCAUUGAUGACCACAUGCUAUAUCUUAAAAUUUUACUGAUAGUUGAUUUUAGCAAGUCUUAUGAAACACUAAGAACAAUGUCUGGUGCCUAGCAAAUUCUCAGUAAAUUUCAGCUAGUAUUAUUACAGUUAGUAUUACUUUACUAUGCUCCCUGAUAAAAUUUUUAUAAUAAAAUGGUUAAUGACUUUCCAUUGAGGUCUGAUCUGACUUAGUUUUAGCAUAAAGUAAUUACAAUUCAUAUUUUUAGAGGUUUUUUUUUUUGUAGUAGUAGAAACAACUAUUUCUAAAUCUGGGGAUUCAGUAGUUCAUUCAAAUUAGGAUCUUUAAGAGCUGUCUAGGUCAAUGUUCCUUAACGUUUUCUACCUGGGAGUAAUCUUUAAGAGAACAAAAAGAAAAUGAAACUCUAUAUAAUUUAAUGCAAAGUCUUUUACAUUAAUGUAAGGGUAGGAAAAGAGGUUGGAGGAAGAUAUGGGGAGGUAGGAAAAUGGGACUUUUUUCCUCCAUUUACUUUUGAUGUUUGAAUUUCAAACAUGAGUAUAUUUGUGUAUUAUUUUGCGGUUAAAAACACUGAAGAUUGCAUAAAGAUCAAAGAGGGAAAUUUAAGGGAAUUAAUGGGUUAUGAUUGCAUUUGUUCAGAAUGGUUUUGGUGGCUCAUGACAACAUUUUGAGAGAGAGAGAUUUUAAUGGCACCAAUGGCAGCUAGGAUAACUAGUUUAAAGUUUAGGGCCUGUGUUAAUAGAUUUUGCUUUCUAGUUUCAGAAAGAUUCUCUUAUAGUACUGUUUUAAUCUGUUUUUCUAAGCCCUCUGAUUUAUGUAUAUUUAAUAGGCCACAAAAUAAUGUCAAAUAUAUGGCAUAAUAACCAACAAAUAUUUGAAUAAGUGAAAGGUACUCUACAAAAUGCUAUGGGAAAGACAAAAAUAAAUAAUAUCCCUUUCUUUGAGGGAUUAACAGUGUUAAUAUCCCUUGUUUUCAUUUGAUUUGAAAUGCCACUUGCAAGUGGAAUAUGCAGACUAAAUGGUAAAGAGAAAAACAAGCAGCAUCUUUUCAUUUCACUUACAGCUCACUGUAUGACCAAUAAUAUGUUACUUGACCUCUCAGCACUCCAUUCUAAAUCCUUAAAUGAUACUUAUUUAGCAUUUCUAAGCAUCUUGAGAUCUCCUCUUAAAAUAUGCUUUGAACUAUUCAGUCUAAAUGCUGCUUUCUAAAAAGCUACUAGUUUAAAGAAUGGGAAAUGGUGUUAAUGGAGUUAAUCUUGUGUAAUUUCAGUGUGGGUUGUCAAGAAUACCUCUAAGUAAAGAAAAUGACUCUAAUCUUCUUAAGCAAUUCAUUUUCUCAGCAACUUUGAGGCAGGAGUUAAUUUACUCUGCCUGUGUACAUAGGCCAUCUCUUACAAAAGAAAAAUUUUACUAUGGAAAGAAGUCAGAAUAGCCAUGAAAUUAUUUAAAUUUAGUCUUUAGAACAUAUUACAAAAUAUAAGAUAUAUUAAAUUGUCUUUUUUGUUAGAAACUCAACUACCAAUGUAGAAAUAAAACUCCUGUUGCAAGGAUGGAGUUUAGCCAUGGAGUCAAAACAAGAGCUAUUUGGUUAUUUUAAAAGAGAAGAGAUCAAAGAGCUGGUCACUCCUUAACUAAGGGUGUUUGGGCAGCAGGAUAGGGUGAAGAGUGGAGGGGGUUGAACUCAAUUCUUUAUGCUUUUAUACCAAGCCUCCCUUUUCUAAUAAGCCUUACUGGCAUUUCCUUAGACUAGUUAAGUCAGGAUUCUGAGUUUUUCAGUACAAUAGGGUUUUAAUCUGAGCUGAUCAUUGUUUCCAAUGCCUCCCCUGUGGCAGGGGAACAUAAAGGACUAGUGUUCUUUUCUAAAAAGGGAAGAUGGAUAUUUUUUCUAUAACCUUUAUAAUUCCAUUAUAAUAAAAUGAAUGAUAGGUUAUAAUAAAAUGAAUUUUUUGCAUAUGAUUUUCAAAAGGAAACUAAUUUAUUUUUCUAUAAAAUAUCGCAAAGGAAUCGAAUACAUUUUUAUUCUAUGUAAAUAAUAAUAUAAUUUUCACAUUUAGGAGGCAAUAGCAAAUCUGGGAAGCAGUUAUUCUAAGUUGGAAGAGCAUUAUCCCAAUGCAUUGAAAACAUUUGAUGACUAUUUUUUAUGUCUUCUUUAUUUUGAUGAUUAUAAUAAUGUUCUAACUGGGUGGCCUUCGUUUUUCACUCUAGUCAGUCCAUCUUGUUUACUAUGUCAAUUGUUCUCCAAAAAGUAGAAAUGUCAUUGUUUUGGGGCCAUAGAACAUUUCAGAAGCUUUCCAGUAUCUAUGCAGUAACAGUCCAAACCCCUCAACAUAACACAUUUACACCUGCAAGUAUGGCCCCAAAUCUUCAAGUGGCUUCUGUCACUACUCCAUAGUACAUACCCUUUGUUACAGCUGUUUCACAAAUACAGGUUGAAUAUCCCUUAUCUAAAAUGUUUGGGACUAAAAGUUUCAGAUUUCAGAUAUGUUUGGAUUUUGGAAUAUUUGUACAUGUAUAAUGAGAUACUCUUAGAGUUGGGACCCAAGUCUAAACAAAAUUCAUUUAUGUUUCAUAUAUACCUUAUACACAUAACCUGAAGGUAAUUUAUUUUUCCCUUGGGAACACUGAAUAGACUAUAUGUUGUGCACCUACAUUUUGACUGUGACCUAUCACAUGAAGUCAGGUGUGGAAUUUUCCAUUUGUGGCAUCAUGUCAGUACUCAAAAAGUUUUGGAUUUUGGAUUUUGAAUUUUCAGAUUAGAGAUGCUCAGCCUAAUAGCAAAUGUUCCCAUGUUAUACACCUCAACCUCCCAUUCCCAUUGGCUGGAACAUCUCUGCUUAUAUUAAAUGUCUUUUAUGUGAAAUCUGUGUUCUCAUAGCCUUUUGUAUAGUUCUCUACCAUCUCAUGGCUCACAUUGUAUUGUACUUAUUUGAUUAAAUAUCUGGAUCAUCUACUGUGAAUUAUUCAAGAGCAUUGAUCUUUAUACCUCUGGCACCUAUCAGUGCCUGACAUAUAACAGGGUUAAAAAUGCUGAGUGAAUACUGCAAAUAUACCUUAGCAAAUUUAUUUGCUGAAUACACAUCUCAAGAAAGUUCUGAAAUAGUUAUUUCCCCUCAUAGAAAGUUUAGAGUAUUAAAAUUGGGUAUCUUUAUAAUGCUUUUUCUUUUGUAAUACUUUCAUCUUUGCCUUUUAUUGAAAUAUUAAAUGCAUUGUAGAAUUUGAUUUAAAAUUUAGAACAAGCUGUCAGGUAUGAUAACUAGUCUCAUUUAACAAAUGAGGAUUCCAGGGCUUGAAGAAGUUAAGUAGCUUCCUCUAGAUUGUAAAGAGAGUCUAACCUGGCCCUUUUUGGUUUUAAGGGCAUGAUGAUAACCACUUGCUCUACUGAUUUCUAAUGGAAAGUGCUUCAGUUUUCCACUUUGCCUAGCUAGUGAUUAUUUAAUAUCUGCUUAUCUCUGAAUUUAUCUGCAUAUUUCUAAAACUUUAUGACAUUAAGGAAAGUUGGGGAAAAUUCACUUUAAGUGUUGUAAUGACAAUAGCUAUCAAUCAUUGAGUACUGUGUACUAAGCAUUUUAUAUUUUAUCAACAAGUACUUACAUGUGGGAUAAGUACUGUUAUUAUUUUCAUUUUAUAGAUGAGGACACAUAUAGAAUGCAGUUAGGAAACUAGAGAAAGAGAAAACAUGGAGAAUUAUCUGGAACUAAUAAGACAGUAAAGUACAGAUUUAAGAAGUUCAGUGAAUCCCAAGCAGUGUAAAUUAAAAAACUACAUUGAGAUACAUCAUAGUGAAUAUGCAAAACAUCAAUAAUAAAAAGAAAAACCUUAAAGGCAGCUUUAACAGUAUACUGAAUGACCAAUAUACUCAGCAGCCACAGAACCUCUAUUCUUUUAAAGCAUCCAUGGGACAUUUAUAGAAAUUGACUAUGCACUGGACUAUAAGCAUAUGCAAUAAAAUUUCAAAUGACUGAAACCAUAUGAGUAUAUUCUUUUGCCACAACACAAUUAGGCUAGAAAUGAACAACAAAAAGAUAACAGGAAAAUCUCUAUAUAUCAGAAAUUAAGAGAUGCACUUAUUUAUUUUUUGUUUUUUGUGAUGGAGUCUCACUCUAUCACCCGUGCAGUGGCACGAUCUUGGCUCACUGCAACCUCUGCCUCUUGGGUUCAAGUGAUUCUCCUGUAUCAGCCUCCCAAGGAGCUAGGAUUACAGGCGUGUGCCACCAUACCCAGCUAAUUUUUGUAUUUUUAUUAGAGAUGGGAUUUCACCAUGUUGGCCAUGCUGGUCUCAAACUCCUGACCUCAAAUGAUCUGCCAGCCUCAGCCUCCCAAAAUGCUGGGAUUACAGAUGAAGAGAUACACUUCUAAGUAAUCUAUAUGUCAAGUAAGACAAAAUGAAAUUAGAAAAUAUUUUUAAGUCAAUGAUAUUAAACCAUACUACACAUCAAAACUUGUGGGAUGCACUUAAAGCAGCAUGUAGAGGGAGAUUAUAUUCAUAAAUGCUUAUGGUAGAAAAGAAGGAAGUCUGUACAUUAUGUAGCUAUGCACCCAUCUAAAGAAGUUAGGAAAAUGACAUCAAGUAGAACAUCAAAAGAAAGAAGGAAAGGAUAACUUAAAACAGAAAUGAAUGAAAUAAAACCAGAAUAGAAGAGACGAUCUACAAAUCCAAAAGUUGGUUUGUUGAAAAUACUAGUAGAGCUGACAUACUUGUGGUGAGACUGAUGGAAAUAAUGCAGUUACAACUAACCAAUAUCAUAAUUGGAAAGGAAAUCACUAUAGGUGCUGUAAAAAUUAAAAAGAUAAUAGAAUAUUAUGAACAAUUUUCUGCCAAUAUUAUUGAAAGUUUAGAUAAAAUGGAAAAUUCAUUUAAAAAUAUAAUUUGACAGUAUUAUGUUAUGUGAAUACUAUAAUGAUAAUCCUGUAAUCAUUAAAUGAACCAGUAGUUUAAAAUUUUUCCAUAUAGGGAAGGUCAGGGCCAGAUGUGUUCAAUGGUUGGUUCUACUAGACAUUCAAAAAAAUAAUAAUUCAAGUCUACACAAACUUUCCUGAGAUUAGAAAAAAUAAAGAAGAGUCCCCCCACCUGUUUCUUACUUUAUGAGACCACACCUAAAAGAUAGAAGACUGCUUUGCAACCAAGAAAUCCUUCAUGAACACCUCUUUAAUCACAAGUCCUCAACUCCAAGGUUAGCUUUAUUUCAACUUUUAUAAUACUUUUCUUACUUUUCUUGAUAGCUUUACCACCCAUGUAUUCAUUCCUAAAAAAUACACAGUUUUGUCUGAUUUUGAAUUUUAUGUGAAUGGAAUUGUACAUAUCUGUGUUUGUGUCUUCCUUGUUUUACUCAAUACUGUUUCUGAGAUCAAUCACAUUAUUUGUUAAUAUUUUGUUUAGGAUUUUUGCAUCUCUAUUUCAGUGUGUGUUUGGAAUGUAAAUUUCCAUUCUCAGACUAUCUUUUGGCCUGAAUUUGGUUACAUGAGUAUAUGUUCUAAAAAUAUUACUUACACUUUCAAUAAAUUUUAAGGACUUUUAUAUUGUUAUGUAUCAAAUUUUUUAGAAUGCAAGAAUAAAUAUUAUAAAACAUC